GAGGUAAUCCAACAGACUGUGGCGGAGGGACCGGAAGCGCCAGGCAGGGACCCGGGGUAGAUGCUAAAUCCAAACUGAAACGUACAGGGCUGGAUGAUUGAAGCACCAGCGGGAACUAGUCGGACCUCCGAGCUCUUUAAACUGUCCUCAGCUCGGCUGGUUCUCCACGAGCUCCGGGCAGACGGCGGGGGGUGGGUCGGCGUUUAAGUCAAAGGCCUUGGGGCUCCGAGUCCCUUCCUCUCCCCGUCCUGUGAAGGCACGACCCAGUUCAGCUGUCUGUAAAGUGGAGCCAUUAGUCCCUGCCUCGUAGUGGGAAAACUGGGAGGCGGAACGAGGAGGCCGCCGGUCCCAACCCGGCCCAGGAGCAUCUUUCUCCGCAGACCGUUUCCUGGCGAGAUCCUGCGCAGCCGAGGCUGUGUUAGCGCCAAGGACUUCCAGCAGCUGUUAGCAGAGCUUGAGCAGGAGGUGGAGCGGCGGCAGCGGCUGGGGCAGGAGUCAGCAGCUAGGAAAGCCCUCAUCGCGAGUUCCUACCACCCGGCACGGCCUGAGGUCUACGACUCACUGCAGGAUGCAGCUCUGGCCCCCGAGUUCCUGGCCGUGACUGAGUACAGCGUGUCCCCAGACGCAGACCUCAAGGGCCUUCUCCAGCGGCUGGAGACAGUAUCGGGUGAGGUCCUGGCCCUGAGACCUGGCAGGACCAGGGAAUGGCAGCCUGGGAAACCUGGGUGUGGGAUGCUGGGGUCCCUCCAGCCACCAUCUCUGCCUCCAAAAACCAAACCAGCAGGAGCUGGAAGGGUCAGUGGGACCAACCUGCCAGGAGCAGGACAUCCGCAUUCAUUCAUUCAAUACCUGCCAUGAGCCUGCCCUGAAAAGCAAAGGCCUCAUCUCCAUGGCACAGGUGAUGAAACAGGAAGACUGAAGCCCAGGCCUGGCCGGCCCACGGCCACAUUCAGGCCAACAGACCAUCCCUCCUUCCACAGAGGAGAAGCGCAUCUACCGGGUGCCUGUUUUCACAGCGCCCUUCUGCCAGGCCCUGCUGGAAGAGCUGGAGCACUUCGAGCAAUCGGACAUGCCUAAGGGGAGGCCCAACACCAUGAACAACUACGGGGUGCUGCUGCACGAGCUCGGGCUGGACGAGCCGCUGAUGACACCACUGCGGGAGCGCUUCCUGCAGCCGCUGAUGGCCCUGCUGUACCCUGACUGUGGCGGGGGCCGGCUCGACAGCCACCGGGCCUUUGUGGUCAAAUACGCACCGGGCCAGGACCUGGAGCUGGGCUGCCACUAUGAUAAUGCCGAGCUCACCCUCAAUGUGGCCUUGGGCAAGGUCUUCACAGGGGGCGCCCUGUAUUUUGGGGGCCUCUUCCAGGCACCCACAGCCCUGACGGAGCCCCUGGAGGUGGAGCACGUGGUGGGCCAGGGUGUCCUCCACCGUGGCGGCCAGCUGCAUGGAGCCCGGCCCUUGGGCACUGGUGAGCGUUGGAACCUUGUCGUCUGGCUCCGAGCCUCUGCUGUGCGCAACAGCCUCUGUCCCAUGUGCUGCCGUGAGCCCGACCUGGUGGACGAUGAGGGCUUCGGUGAUGGCUUCACCCGAGAGGAGCCCGCCACGGUGGAUGUAUGUGCGCUCACCUGAGCUUGCUUGGGCCCAGUGUGGGGGUGGCAGGCAGGUGAGGGCUCCGUUGCCUUGGUCUGGGGGCAGAAAUAAAAUCCCCGCAGCCUACUGCACUUCUUGGCUCAACGGUGUGCCAGCUUCUGGGUCAUUCUAUGGGCAAAGAUGCUGCCUUAGUUCAGGUUUGUCAGAAGCAGGGUCUGGAAUGGGGCUUCAGCGAGGGAGUCAGGGAAGCAGGGGAGGGGAGGGAGCAGCUGGGCAAGGAAGUGGCUUCAGAGGACGUCCAGCCUCAGCUGGCCCCACGGAGAGCUCCAGGCAGAGCCCACAGUACCACAGUGUGCCCACACCACCGGUUACUGGCUCCUGGAUGAGGGGGCCAGAGAGGAGUGAAUAACUUCCCAGACACUUAUCUCCAGGGCAGGGUGCCUUCCAGUAGCCAAGGGAAGCCUCCAGAGAGCACAGAUGUGAACCCUCAGCAGCAGGCAUCACCCCCCAGUGGACUCGGGUGGGCCACCAGUAGCAUCUUCUAGAUGGCAGAGGGGUGAAUGGCAGGGCCAGGAACCAGGCUGCCCGGGUUCCCAUUCUGCUUCUGCCACUUCCAGCUGUGUGGCUUUAGGUGAGCCUUCACCUUUUGGUGCCUUCGUUUCCUCAUUUAGCACCUACCUCCUAGAGCUGUUUUGGGAGUCAAAUGCGCUGACGUAUAUAAAGUGCUUUGCAAGA